GGAGCCUGCGGAGUUCGAGACCAUGCUGCUGUUCUGCCCCGGCUGCGGGAACGGGCUGAUCGUGGAGGAGGGACAACGCUGCCACCGCUUCGCCUGCAACACGUGCCCCUACGUGCACAACAUCACCCGCAAGGUAACAAAUCGGAAGUACCCAAAACUGAAAGAAGUGGAUGAUGUGCUUGGUGGAGCAGCUGCCUGGGAGAAUGUUGACUCUACUGCAGAGUCGUGUCCCAAAUGCGAACAUCCUCGUGCUUACUUCAUGCAGCUUCAGACCCGCUCUGCAGAUGAGCCGAUGACCACCUUCUACAAGUGCUGCAAUGCUCAGUGUGGACACCGCUGGAGGGAUUAGGGCCAGGAUGGCCCAGCUGCCCUAGUGUGUGCUUGCCUUGUCCCUCGGGGUAGAUGCUUAGCUGGCAGUAUGAGUUGUGUGUCCUGAGGGUCUUUGCUAGUGUGGUGGAAAGAUAAACCUUUUGAGGUGAAGAGCCAGGGGGUCAGGAAAUAUGGCCUAUCUGCCAGGCAGGGUGGAUGAAGUCAUGAAUGUCUGGGAGUUUUUCUGUGUGGGGAGGAGACAGAGACCCAUAACUAAAUAUGCUCUGUGUAAAGUCCUAUUCUUUCAUCUUCCACUUUAUUGGCAGUUGACAUUCCCUUACUCCCAAUCAACACUCUUAAAUAUUUGUACUGUUUGUAAAACUUAGUACAUGUCCCUAAAUAUUUAACUGUUACUUGUAAACUUGUGUAAUUUAUUAUUUAUUUUAAUCAAAAUUCUGAAUAUUUCAUUUAAAUGAAAGUUGGAAUAUUGCCUUCUCAGUGUUUUAAAUAGCUUAAGAGGUAGAAAGCAAACCCCAAAUCACAGUGAUCCCAGAAUAGACUACAUACUUACAUUUGAACAGGCUACGAAAAUGUUAAUCACCGGGAUUUCAAUUUCUUUCUUUAUUCCUAUUCUUACUCCCUUAUUCAUUUUUUUGAACCUCCCCUGAUUUGCUUCCUCGGGUUGCUUUAAAUGUAUAAGAUACUAUUUAUUUAUUUAUUUAUUUUAUUUAUUUAUUUAUUUAUUUAAGACAGAGUCUUGUUCUGUCGCCCAGGCUGGAGUGCAGUGGUACGAAUUCAGCUCACUGCAACCUCUGCCUUCCGGGUUCAAGGGAUUCUCCUGUCUCAGCCUCCCAAGCAGCUGGGACUACAGGCAUGCACCACCACACCUGGGUAAUUUUGCAUUUUUAGUAGAGAUGGGGUUUCUCCAUGUUGGUCGGGCUGGUCUCCAACUCCUGACCUCAGAUAAUCUGUCUGCCUCGGCCUCCUAAAGUGCUGGGAUUACAGGCGUGAGCCACUGUGUCCCACCAAUCUUUACAUUUAAUAUGACUAUUUUCUUAUUGUU